GCAGUCGGAGCGCGGCGGCAGCGGCAGAGGCGCCGCGGCGGGGACCAGCCCAGAGAGACCCCCCGAGCCCGCGGCACAGGCGGCGGCGGCGCUGAGCGGGCUCGACCAGCCGAGCGAGCGGCGGCCCCGGCUCCUCCUCGUCCGGCGCCAGCAGCCCGCGCCCCGCGCCCGCACUCGGCCAGCCGAGACCCGCCUCCCGCCCGCCCGCCGGCCUCGUGAGGGACGCGCCGAGCCGGGCGGCCGAGAGCGGCGGCGGCUGGGAGCGCGUCGGGCCCGGGCGGAAAGUGCCUGCGGGGGGCGGGCGAGCGCGCGGUGCCGGCCGCCCCGGGGCUCGGCGCGGGAGCCAGAGCGGGAGCCGGCGCGGAGCGGGACGCCGGGUCCCGAGCGGCCCGCGGCCGGGGCUCGCCCCCGCCCCUCCCUCCUCUCCGGCGGCGGCGGCGGCGGCGGCGGGCGGAGUGAGCUGCGGAGCCUGGAAUAUGGUCGGGGAAAUGGAAACGAAGGAGAAGCCGAAGCCCACCCCAGAUUACCUGAUGCAGCUGAUGAACGACAAGAAGCUCAUGAGCAGCCUGCCCAACUUCUGCGGGAUCUUCAACCACCUCGAGCGGCUGCUGGACGAAGAAAUUAGCAGAGUACGGAAAGACAUGUACAAUGACACAUUAAAUGGCAGUACAGAGAAAAGGAGUGCAGAAUUGCCUGAUGCUGUGGGACCUAUUGUUCAGUUACAAGAGAAACUUUAUGUGCCUGUAAAAGAAUACCCAGAUUUUAAUUUUGUUGGGAGAAUCCUUGGACCUAGAGGACUUACAGCCAAACAACUUGAAGCAGAAACCGGAUGUAAAAUCAUGGUCCGAGGCAAAGGCUCAAUGAGGGAUAAAAAAAAGGAGGAGCAAAAUAGAGGCAAGCCCAAUUGGGAGCAUCUAAAUGAAGAUUUACAUGUACUAAUCACUGUGGAAGAUGCUCAGAACAGAGCAGAAAUCAAAUUGAAGAGAGCAGUUGAAGAAGUGAAGAAAUUAUUGGUACCUGCAGCAGAAGGAGAAGACAGCCUGAAGAAGAUGCAGCUGAUGGAGCUUGCGAUUCUGAAUGGCACCUACAGAGAUGCCAACAUUAAAUCACCAGCCCUUGCCUUUUCUCUUGCAGCAACAGCCCAGGCUGCUCCAAGGAUCAUUACUGGGCCUGCGCCGGUUCUCCCACCAGCUGCCCUGCGUACUCCUACGCCAGCUGGCCCUACCAUAAUGCCUUUGAUCAGACAAAUACAGACCGCUGUCAUGCCAAACGGAACUCCUCACCCAACUGCUGCAAUAGUUCCUCCAGGGCCCGAAGCUGGUUUAAUCUAUACACCCUAUGAGUACCCCUACACAUUGGCACCAGCUACAUCAAUCCUUGAGUAUCCUAUUGAACCUAGUGGUGUAUUAGGUAAGUUCUUCUCCCCAUGGGGUUAACAACAUUCUCUUUAUAAAUAUUUUUGCUCCCUCAGAUUUUGAAAUGAUUUUAUCAGUUUUAGAGAGGCAAGACAAGUUUGCAUUAGGGAAGACCGAAAACUAAAUUUUGUUUUAUUUCAGCCUCUCAUAAGGGUUCCCCUUUGAAAUAAUUGCACCUUAAAUUUAUUCAGAUCCACUUUGGUAACUGAGGUUCAGUUUGGUUGGGUAAAUCUGUUGUGUACAUUUCAACAAAUACUUUUACAUUUGACAUUACUGAGGUCAUUCUGAGUUUUAGGUCCCACCCCAUUGGCCCGUCACCUCCAUCAGCUCCACUUCUCAAACUUUAUUUGAGAUUUAUUUUAUCUCACAGGUUUGUGUAAUUGUUGGAAAAUUUUUAAACUUCUAAGUGAAAGUAGUCUGAGCGCUUUAUAAAAUUCAUAUUAUUGUGUGUGUUUUGUAAUAUUUGCGAUCACUUAAAAUAUCAGAUAAAUACAGUCAUGCAUCGCUUAACAACGGGGAUACAGUCUAAGAAUUGCCUUGUCUGGCAGUUUCAUCAUUUGGUGUACAUCAUAGAGUGUACUUACACAGACAUAGAUGAUAUCGUUUACUACACACCUAGGCUGUGUGGUAUAGCCAUUAUAAUCUUAUGGGACCACAUAGUAUAAGUGGUCCGUUGUUGACCAAAAUGUUGUUAUGCAGGCAUGACUGUAGUUGUAUUCUUAAGAUUUUUCAGUUCUUGUGUUUUGGAGUCCUAGUCAUAUUAAACAUGAGAGAUACUCUUAAUUUCAGUAGUACAGUAUGGAAUAGUUAAAUAAAUAGCAAAUCACUGAAUUCAGAAUCUCACUUAAGGCAGAAAUUAAAAUCAUAAUAUAAACGCUUGGUUUUACAUGAACAAAAAGUGGUGUGCUCGAAAAAGACAUUACUGAUGCCUUUUUUUUAUAGAGUGGAUUGAAAUGCCAGUCAUGCCUGAUAUUUCAGCCCAUUGACUUGCUGGAUGAAGGACUAGAAUACAGCAGCUGUUAUAACACGACCAGUCAAUGUGGAACAAACUGUUUCUGUGCAACCCCUUUGUUUUACCAGACAAAAUUUGAAUACUUUUUUUCCUGAAUUGUAUAUGACCUUGGUGCUGCAUGCAUGCUGUUGACUUUUAGGACUUUGAUCUUUUAAGGUUUUUUUUCCCCAGCAUUAAUAUUGAUUUAUAAAGAUUUGAAAAUCUUUAAUGAACUGGAGAACACUAAGAUUUAAACUCGAAAAUUCGUUGUUCAAGUAAAGAAAGCCAUGAUGCUCUGUAUGUUAUCUGUGUGUGUGCAUGCACUCAGGUGCCCUUUGUUUCAUGAACAAAUACAUUUCAUUGUACAUGUUUUCUGUUUAAAUCAUUGUAUAAAGUAAUUGCAGGUCAGAAUUAUACCACAGAACUGUUUAUGAGAGGCUUGUGUCUGUUGCACAUUUCUUGAAGCAUUUUUAAAAUAACAUGUAACCUGUAACCUUGUUGUUUAAGUUUUCUUUUCUAUUAAUACUCUGUCCUGUGGUCCCGUGCAUGCUCCUUUUCCCAGAACUCCUCUCUGCUGCACCCACAGCAUCUGUUCCCGAGGAGUUAUGACUCUUGACUUCCUGCAGGGCUGGGGCUCUUAGCCACCAGCUGCUGUUCCAGCACUUUCAGCGCAAGAUCUCCCUGAUUUUGCCACGUGGAAUUGUACUUGUAUAUGAUUACCUUAUCUAAAAUGAAUAAGAGGUGAUGGACCAGUUUACUGCUUAGAAAUAGCAAGAGGCACUGCAGUAAAACUUGUUUCUCAUUGUAAAGCUUCAUGUCUUUUGUUUGUUGGAAAAUUUUUACUUAUAGAAACUUAAUUAUUAGACUGGUAAAAUAAAGACCAAAAUAUGCAGAUUUCUAAUUGGCAUUCAUAAGGUGAAUAAUAAUAAGUGCCCAAUGAAAAAAUCUAUUAUGGUUAAUUUCAUUUCUUGCUUUGCCACCUAAGCAGUAAAACAUGAUAUUGACCACUUGGAGAACUCAGAAAAUUAUUUUAAAUUUCUAAGUUAUAAUAAAUUUGCACACAGAUAACAUGCAUGCUAUUUAUGUCACAUCUCACAUUAAAUUAUUUUAAAAUAAGCAGUGCCCUUCAAAACAGAUGCAGACAUGUGUGUUGGUAGUAGUGAGGAGAUUGGUAUUAGCAUCAAGUCUUCAUUGAUGACUAAUUUUUAAUUCCCUUCCUUUUAUCUUUAGGUAUGGCUUUCCCAACGAAAGGCUAAGAAUUCAAGAACGGUCUUAACUGAACCCUCAUCAGAUCUGAAUUUAACAAAUGCUUAGUCUCAGCAGCCUCCGGGGGAAAAAAGCUUAGCCUAGCAGUCAGUGACUUACUUGCACUUUUUGCACAUAGAUAUAAAGUAAAAUUAUGUUAUUAAUUUGGUUUAGUCUGUAAUAUUACACAGUAAUGGUAAUUUAUAAAGGAGUGUAUAGUAGUAUACUGACUGCUAAGUGUACUAUACUGUUUGCUUUACUAAUCACCUAAUUCAUUGCAGUUCAUACUUAUUGACUCAGAGUUUAAAACCACAAUCUGUAGGCUUUAAGAAUUGCUUUUAAACCUUUUUAAGUGAUAAACUCUUGAAGUGGUCUUAAGGUUAGCAAAUAAUUGUCUGUAUUAAACAUGGCGUUAUUUAAGUAGUCCUGCUGCAAGAAAGGCACUUCAGUGAAUAUGUGACUAGUAAAGCUUAAAUAUGUUUGGAUCUAAUAGAGCUCAUGAAAUACUGUAACUUGGGGAUUGUAAAUGAAUGGAUACAAUAGGUUAAGGCCCAAGAUGUUUGAAAUGAAUGCAAUAUUAAUAGAUGCAUAUAUACAUGACAUAUUGUGGUUAAUUUUAAAACUACUGUGCCUUAACGUGUUUCUUAAACUUUUGUAGUAAAUGAACAUUUGAAAUCCAUUUUGAUAAACCUGCUGUUAAUGUUUUUUCCCCCCUUGUGAAUGUUUUCUAACUUUGUCUUGGUAAUUGCAAUUUAACUAGGUGCGGUGGCUACUAAAGUUCGAAGGCACGAUAUGCGUGUCCAUCCUUACCAAAGGAUUGUGACCGCAGACCGAGGUUAGUUUAGUUCUGCAGUUCUUGUCUAUAAGAAAUGCGUUGGGUGUCCAUAAAAUUUGCAACACCACACCUGAUGGAAAAAUGUAAUUGCUUACCUGCACACAGUUUUUUUUCCUUUUCUAAAUUUGUUUGUGAUCAUUGACAGAUUUAAGGGUUGGGUUUUUUGUUUUGGUUUGGUUUUUUCUCCCUUCAUAUUUUAACUUAUUAAAUCUUCUAUUAUUAUGUACUAUGAUUUAUUCCUACUAAAACAUAAAUUAGUCAAUUUGGGGAGCUAUUAAAUUUUGAUGUUGCCUCAGUUAUUUUCAUUAAUAACUUUUGCUAAAAUUUACCUUUUAAAAGUUCUGAAAUUUGGGGUUGGUAUUGCAAAAUGAAUUGAACGGAUGGUGCUUUAAUGAGAGAAGUAAAGGAAUAUAUGCCUCCUGUGUACUUUUGGAGAAAACUGAAGAUUUAGUUUCCAUUUUUCUUUAUAAUAAAAUAUUUGAGCCACUGUAUAAACAUGAGGGUGCACAUGUCAAGUACUUAGCUAAAAUCAACAAAGUGAGGACUGUGAAGAUAACUUUCAUGUAGUUGGAUUUUUUUAUAUAAAUUAGAGCGUCAAUUCCCUUUUAUUCUUACAUUCUCUUGCCAAAAUGGAUCCUUUGAUUUUUGUCAUUUGCUGCUAAAAUAUAUUAUCUGAAGGUAAACUGUCUCUUGAAGUUCUGUGGUGGUAUGAGAUCCAGCUGUGUGAAUAUAAUUUUUGACUAACCUGUGACUGGAAAAUAAGUCUUCAUUUUUCUCCUUUACAACUUUUAUAAUUUGUGUCCUGUAUAUGCCCUUGGACCCUUUUAUAAAUUAUUUUUGCUUAUUGAGGAAUGGUAUUUUCGGUUUAUUGACAUUGAAUUGUUUUCUAAGUUUUUCCAUCACAAGAUAGGAAUAUCAAGCAUGGUAGUAAAAAAGGAUUUUUUACAAGUUUCUAUUAUGGCACAUUUGUUUCCUACAAAUUAAAUUGAUCAAAGUCUCAAAUAUUAGUGGAGGAAAAAGUGCUGGAUUUGUACUUCAAUUGUACAUCUUCUAUGAAUUUAUGAAGGACCUACCUGCUUUAUGUGAUUACCUUGAGUACUGAUGAUAAAUACUAGACACAGCUGUUGUCCACAUCAGAAAUAACAUGCCUUUCCCAAAGACAUUGUUAAUAUUUGUUUAGCAUAAUCCAUAAAGAACGUUGAAGACUUUUAAACUAAUGUAUUCAUCACUAACAGUGAUUGUUCAGUGAACAAAAUAGACCCCAGCUCCGUGGUCGUCUAUGAGGAUGGUAUUCCUUGUAAGUGUUCUGUAUGAGCACGUCUCAUAGGGAUGGGGAAGUUUUUUGGAAAGUCACUUGAGUUUUAAAGAAACUGGACAAUUCCAUGAAUAAUUUGAGGUUUUAUUCAUAUUGCUAAUGUCUACAAUUGUUCUAAAGAGUAUUUUAAAGUAGUUUUUUUCCCCCAGCUAAUCUUUCCCUAUGUAUGCCCCCUUUUAGGAGAUUUCUCACCAUUUUGCUUUAACACAAUAAUUAUUGGCCUACUUAAUACUCCAGUGCCUUGAGAUAGUUGGACAUAUUUUAGGAAGAUUUUAUUGUAUUUGGAAAAUUACGACACAUUCCAUGCAUGGAUCUUUUGUAGUUACGUGUUUUGAUUAGUCCUGUCACUGUUUUUAUUUAAAAUGCAGUGUCAGCAAACCGAAAUGCUCAUUUCUUUUUUAGUAACAGAGUACUCGUAUACUUAUCACUGUAUGCACUCAUUGGGUCUAAGGGAGAUGUCUGAAGUCCUUCACUUAAAUUAUUUUAUGAUACUACUGUUUUCUCUAUUUUUGAGGUUAAAAUUAUUUUAAAAAAAUAUUUUGAAGAGAAGUUUAUUAGUAUAAGCAUUCAUUUAAUGCAAAAAAACUCAGCCCUUGGACAUAUAACCAUGUAAUUCUAUAUGAACGUUUAGAGUACUACAUGGUUGACCAAUAUCUAGUUCUUUACUAAAAGUAAACUCACCUCUUUAUAUAUAUUUCAAAACUGAAUUUGAAGCCUAUUAGAGACCAACUGACCUUUUAGUUGUAAUGAACUGUAUGGUCUUGCAUGGUGACACACCUGUGUAGGAGGCCAAGACUUGGCAGAGGAUGUAGUCUAGGUGUCCUGGUAUAUAUAAAUGGUCACUCACUUCGUUUAUAUAUUCCACACUCAGAAAAGAAGUCAGAGUUUUUUCUGAGUAAUACAAAAACCAUCACUUACAUAAUUUGUAUAAGAAACUUUAAACAGUUUUAAUCAAAACUAUGAGUAACAUCAAAAAUGCUUUAAGAUUCUAUAUUUUGGAAUACCUGUGAAGUAGUAUGACUACAUCAUGUUAAAUAUUUAUUUUCUUCUAUGAUUUUGGAGCAGCAAUUUUUAUUUUAAAUAAAAUUCCACUUUUAAGAAAUUCAGGGAAGAUUUGGUCACAUUGAAGAUACAGUAUUUUUGUAGUAUUUAUAAACUGUUCUAAAUGAUAGACUAUAGAAAACAUUUUUGUCAUAUGAAGGUAAAUCAGUCCAUUAUUUUGGAUCAUUUAAACUGAACAUUACACCUUCUGGGCUUUGAUUUAUGAAGUGGCACAGAAUCUAACUUUGCACUGAAUAUCUUUUCAUUCACAUCUCCUCUGCCUUAGUCACAAUGGCAACAGUACAGAAAAUUCUAUCAAACCUCAGAAUAUAGUAGAAAUAAUUAAGCUGUUGAAUGAGUCUUAAAAAUUAUACUACUGUUAAGUGGACCAAGUUUGGUGAAGCAGAAUGUGACAAAGGUUGAUUAAGGAAGGAACAACUCAAGGACAUUGGGAAUGAUAACUUUUCCACUUGAGAACUACUUUAUGUUUUACUGUAAUUUUUAAAGUUUUUUUGUCCUUUUUGUUAUUUUGCAAAAGAAAAUAGUAUUUACAGGUGGCUUCUUUUAAAAUAUAAAAAUAUAAAGCAGGAAUGUAUAUGAAAUGUCAGAUUUUAUUGUAUUUGCAGAGUAUUAGCUUUGAAAUUGAAUAAAGAAAGCUGUUUGUAGUUUUAAAAUGCCUUAUUGGUAUCAAUUAGAAAUUUCUUCUAUUUUUUGAUGUACUUAGAGCUUUUUGAGUGUAGAAUUUUAAAUGGCAGGAUUUUACAGUGUUUACAUGCAAGUGCAUUUUAUAAGUGUUCUAUAUGUGUAAAAUAGUAUUUUCAACUGGAAAGUGUUGGCUAGUGCAAAAGGCCUGGCCAUUUUCUGGUUCCCAUGAUGUUGCCUACACUGCUAGACUACAGUUUAGUAUCGCUUUGUAUCAUGAGGCCAAGAAAUUCCAUGUUGUUUGUAAAUAGAAUAAUUGAAAAAGCAAUAAACAUUUAUUGAACAAAAGAAACCUUGUUUGGCCCAGAGUUUAUGUUGAACCAAAUGGUUCAUAGAAUUUUGAAUUUCUUUAGAUUCAUUUCUGUUAAUCAUCAGUUAUUAAUAAUCACAUCCAUCAUUAAUAGUUGCUUUAAUGCUUGCAUCUUAGAGAAUACUAAUGCUUAAUAGCAGUCAGAUACUGAUAACUGCACUGACUGUUUAAAAAUUCUGUAUACCAAACCUAUUCAUUGUUGUUUUUCAAUUUCCUUCAUUGACUGCUACUAACUAUUAGUUGUUAGUUGUAUUUUAUUUCUAUUUUUUCUUGUUAACCAGUUUUUUUUUUUUUUUUGUGGGAGUGGGCUCUUCUUCAUUUGUUCAAAUCAUGAUACGAAAUUGUCAUGAUUUUAAUUGUAUUCUGUAGAUGGUGUCAAUCAGUUUGUCAGAAUUAAACAUGCUUUUUUUUUUAUUAGUUGUGAUUAGUUUUUCAUGUUGUCAUUAAGCCGUCACUAGCUGAAACUAAUCUCUUCUCUAUCUUUUCUUUUCUUUUUUUUGUUUUGUUUUUUUUUGUUUCUAACCACCCAGCCGCCACCGGCAACUAACCUAUGACCUUCUGACCUCUGAACUCUUCACCCAAUGAUGACCUGACCAUGCCUGCCUGCUGAUCAGUUAACUGGUAAUCGCCUUUGCUUGCCUGUCGUCAGUGCAGCGAGCUGAGGCACUUGUCCGUUCGUCUUACCAUCUAACCAAACAAAAGACAAAGAAAUUGUUGUCCUCCAACUCAGCUUUUUUUUUUUUUUUUUCCUGUUUGGGUGAAAGUGGUUCUAGAAACUGCACUGAAUAGUAGUAAAGCAAUAAGGCCCAAUUCAUCCCACAGCACUGAUCAUCUUUUAAUAUCCCACCCUAAGCGAACGGUAAGAAGGCCUCUCUUAAGAAGGGGAGACAGAUGGUCCUUAACUACUCAAUGACAGAGGCAGUUACUGUGAGAGACUUCUAGGAAUCUUUUUCUUCUCAUAGCGAAGUCAAAGCUCUCUCUGAAUGUACUGUGUGAUGAUGCAUCAUGCAUGAACCUUCGGUCAGGGAUAUCAUUGGUGAAGUGAUUUCAAAAAGUAUUCAAAAUUUGAUAUGCUGUUUAGUCACUACAGUGCCCUCAAAGGGCAGAAGUUGCAGCCUUUUUUAUAUUGCCUGCCAAAAUUUGAAGUAUUAGAAGAAAGUGUGCCAUGAGAGAAAAACUUAAGGAGUUUUGAAAAGUAAUGCAAAUAACAAAACUGCAACACUAUUUUUAAAAAGAUAAAUAUCUGAGUUAAAAUUACUGAAUCUUUAUUUUACACCUAAAAAAAUAUGAGAACAAGGUACAUGCAUUAUGUGUCACAUUACUGGGCAAACUGUUCAAGUAUUUUUUUUUAAACCUCCCUGUAUAGAAAAAAAUCAUUAAGGAUGUAAAAGCCAUGCUUGCCUAUUUGCUGUAUACAUGUAAUGAAAUUGUAGAUAAAGUGUAGUGCAUUGAAACAAAUGAACAAAAAGUAGAUACUUUUACUAUACAAGGGUGCUGGUGCAGAAAAAAAUAUAUAUAUUUUUGGAAAUGUAGCAUUUUAUACUUUCAAGUGUUAUAAAAAAAAAGAAAAAGAACAAAGAAACCCUUUAUUUCAUUAAAUGAUUUUUUCUGGUGGUUGUCAAGAAACAAAAGACCAAAAGAGCCUUUUUGUCUUUCUUUUUUAUUUUUUAAGUAUUGGAAUAAGUCUAAAGAAAAGAAAGUGCCUUAUUUUCCUUCAUGGUCAUUCAGUCAAGUGUCUCAUAAAGAUCAGCUCCUCCCUCAGAAUACAAGUUAAUGCAUGUUACUCAGUCGCCCAGUAUGUGAAAGAAGAUAUGAGGGAGACAAAUGAGUUGAUAGUUUGAAUUAUAGGAUUUUUGCCACGUUACCUUGAUGCAAAUUUGCCAAAUCUGAUACUGUGAAAAGAUUUGAUAACUUUUCUAAUGCCUGACUAGUAAGUUUUAAAACAUCAUUCUUUAAAAGAAUAGUUUAAUACUUUUGGUUAUUCCAAUCUUCAAUGUUAACCCAAAGGAUUCUGAGAUAAAAAUUAUGUGUCAUCUAAACUUCAGUUUACAGACAAAAUUAGAGCUUUGUUUUAUUUGGAGAAGGGGGAUGCAUUCAUUUGAUUUUGUUUUUUGUUUUUAAUUAAUUGAAUAUAAUAGGAUACCUAGCAAAUGUUUUCACAAAAGUGAAUCUUUGUGAUUUUCAUUCUAGAAAACAAUGUUUUAAAUCACCCAAAUUUAAUCACAUGUCUUUAUAUCAUACCAGAUAACUGGUGUAGUGUAUCCUUUUACUGUUUCAAUAACCUCUGCCUCCCCCACCCCUUAACUUUAAAAGAAUGUGAAAAACUAGCAUCAUAGUGCAUAUAAAUACUCAACCACAUUUCAGCUUAAGCUUCUAAUUUCUCAAGAAGUUGAAACAGUUAGUUAUGUAGUUGAAGCAAUUUGUGUGCAAAGCCUACAUCUAAACACUUGAGUGAAUAAUCAUUAACUGCUCAGUACCAGACGUGGCAAAUCUCAAGUGACAGUGGACCCCCCCCCCCGCCCAGCUUAUCAACUCGUCCCCUCUUCCACACCUUCCCAGCAUCACAGUCAGAGGUCAGCAGGAAGCUGAGUCAUUACCUUCUUGGUGACCUCCCCCACCAUCUUGUCUCACUUGGAAACCGUUGUCAGUUUAUUUACUAUGCAAUAGACAUUCAUUGUUUUGUAUCCAGCUAGCUUUGGUUUAAUAUGCCACUGCUUUGUCUUUCUGUUACACAUACAGUUUUGAUUUAUUUACAAUAUAUGCUGUGCCAUUUUGAUUUUUAUAUUGUUUGGUUGGUUGAAUAAAUUUGCGACACUCAAACACUUGAGGUGAUAGUUGUUAAAAACAAUACCAGUAUUUGAUCCAGUUUCAUCUCAACUAUGUUAUACCUGGACAUUUUAGAUGUUUAUCAAAGGUCUUUUAUGGGGAAGAAAGUAAAUGUAUGAAAUAAUAAAUGUGUGACAUUUAUAGGGAAUGUUGGCUCUGAACAAACUUUUGAAAACUUGGUUGACAAAAUUUUGGAUCAACUGAAAAAAGCAUGACUUUUGAAAUCUCUGAAUGCCUUGGUUCUCAGUAUUAUCAUUCUUUAUUGAAUUUAUUUCUUAUUAAAAUAUGUAGUUUUUAAGACUUUUUUUCUGACAGUAUUAUGUAAUUUUUUAGCGUGGGUAGAUGGGAGUGUCGCUUGUAUGUUAUCGUACAGCUGACAUGUAUUUUUGUCUAUUCUUUAUUAUCUUAGUUUCAUGCUAUGUAUGUACCAUAACCAACCUAUUGCCUAUGAGAAACAUGUAAGAUAAUGUAUUUACAGCCAUUGUUACAAGUUUAUAAUGUAUUUUUCUAUCUUGUUUUAUAUGUAUGUUAUAUAACAUUCAAAAAGAAUUUUUUUCUUGAUUGAGAAAAGGAUACAAAAUGCAAAAUCCACAAUUUUGAUAACUGAAAAUUGCCAAUUGUUUUGCAGUACUUUAUUAUAUUGGGUGUCUUGUCUUUUUUGGGCUUUUAGUUAGCUAAUGAAUGAAUACAUUAGACACUUUUGGGUUUUAGUUGGGAUUUUACAUAGCUUGCAUUUUAAUUCUUUGGUUCUUUGCUGUUUCUAUUAACCCACAGCAUUAUUUUAAUAAAUGUUAUAAUACCAACCUACUAACUCUGGACUUUGUCUGUUUAUUAACCUUUAUAUGUUUAAUUAAAAUAAACAAAUAAAGACAAAAGAAUGUAAAGUCUUGAGUUACUGGACUAACCCUGAAGAACGUGACCACAGAUAACAUAGUGUGACUUGUUUUUAUGUUGUUUGUCAGCUGACAGUUUUGCACACUACUGUUAAAAUGGCUUUGGUUAUUCUGGUCUUUUAGCUUGGGGGCCGGGGCGGGUGUGGGUGUAGGUGCAGUAGAGAUGGGAACAAAGUAGCCUUUGUUUGAGGCAUUCUUCUCUUGCCACUUGCCUUUCAGCAUCUGCAUUACUAAUUCCACACCUUAUUUUUCCUUCUCCAAAAUAAUCACUGUCUGCUCACAGCAUCGAGUAAAAAGAUACAUUGUCAUGGUAUAUACCUGGAGAAACCAGUUUGAUUCUUUGUUGAACCAUUUCUUUUAAUUUCUGUAAAUAAGUAAUUUUAUGGUCACAUUGUAAAGCAGAGAAACUGUUGAUAUUUUACCUUUAUUUAGAUUUUUGUUUUAACUUGACCUUUUUCCUUUGGAAAGCGUUGAACUUGUUUAGCUAACUACUCCUAUUAGGGGAGCUUAACUUGGGUAAAGUCAAAGGCCCACUGGCUGUUUCUCAUGGUGGCCUGAAGCCCCGCUGCUUUCCAGUGAGGAAAAGAACCCUCAGCACGUUACUGAGCUUUCCUCAGGUAUUUUUUUCUCUGUCACCUACUUUACAAAUACAGUCAGACUAAAACAUUAAACAAGAAGUUUAAGGGGGAAUAACAUUGGGAUUUGAAAAGUUGUAUGUGAUUAAUUUCUUGCAUGCAAAUCAAUUUAAGAUUUCUUAAAUAUCUUCAUGCUUUUCUUGGCUGGAACUUGGGUAAAUUAACCUGUAAUUAUGAAUUAUUUAGUUUAACUCAAGGUGCAUUUUUAUUUCACAGAUUGAUACUUGCUUUUUUCUGUGAAACAGUUCUCCUAGAUACCAAAAUCCUCAGGAUGAAUUUUUGCAUUUGUAAAUAACAAUUUAUCUUUGUAAAUUACAUUUUAUUUAUUUAGAGUUCUAAAAUUGAGGGCUGAAAUGAAUGACAUGUAAUAGAAGACAAAACUGUACCAAUACGCUGUUAACCAAUCAGACUGUCCAGGUAUUCUCAUUUCAUAAAUAUGUAUACACACAUAUAAAUACACAGAGUAGUGUUAGCUGAUGUGAGUGAUAACAGCGAAUCACCAUUGAGAUGGUCAUUUGGAUCAUGUAAACAAACCGUGUCAUGUCUCUGAUGGGAGCGGUGGGUAGUGUACUGUUAGGUGGACAGGUCUUUUAACAUGCUACUAUUUGUAAAAGUUUCCGUUGCCAUAACAGUUCAUGUAGUAGUCUGUGAAAAUUCGAAGCUGUCUGUCAAGCUGCUAAUAUACAAGUUGUCAUGGUACCAUGUAACUUAAAUUGAUGAAUUUCUAUGCAAUUUACUAUUCUCUGAAGCCUAUGAAUGCAGCCUCAUCUCAUUUUCAGUUAAGGGUACUUUAUGUAUAAUUAUGUCAUUGCUGCCUUUUAUGUAGGAAAUGUAAAAAAGUUUUAAAAGGCGAAAAUAACAUUACAGAUUUCAUUUUUAUACAGGUUACAAUAUUAAACAUGAAACUACCAAAUUCCAAGAAUAGUAAAAUUCUAGAGUCAGUUGAUUGAUUGAAACUAUUUGACAAAACAGUUGAAAGCUGAGCUUUCAGUCAAGAAGUUGGUGAAAUUAAUGUCCUUAAACUUUUCCUUUAGGCAAAAUGUCAGGGAAAACUUAACAUGAAAGUAGUUACUCCCAUACGCACCAGUGCAGUAGCUCCAGGUGUAAGAGGUCACGAAGGCACCCUGCCCAUAAAACCAGGAUGUGCAUACGUACACACAAUCGGUGUCUGGUUAUGGUUUUCUAAACACUACAUAAGGAUCUGAAUUUUUUAGUGUGCCAAAAGCAAACGAUAGGUUUAAAUGAAAUUGCUCACUACCAAAUCAAGACUCUUCAUAUAUAUACGUGUGUGUAUAUAUAUAUGUCAUAACACUUUCACGUGUGACAGCCUAAGGUUUCUUUAGUUUUAGGAUGGGGUGGGGUGGGAGUGGUUUUGCAUGUUUGACCAGGAUGUGAUGCCUGUCUUUAUUCCUUGAUAAGAAGUAGCUGUUACAGCAUUUCAAGCAAAUUAUUUUAGGUAGAAUAGAACUUACUGCCAAAUGAUUAUUUAUUUAGCAAAAAUUAUUCUCCAACUUUUCGAAUUCACAAUUUUUCUAAGUGCAUAGAGUAGUUUUUUACAUUGUCACGAAUUCCUUAAUACCUUUAUUUAAAAUGGAAAAAAUAUGGACAAUAUUUUAGAAAUAUGUGCUACACAUCUAAUUUUAUCUGUAGUUUAAGUGAUCUAAAUUGAGAUGCCUUUGAUAUGAAGAGAUUUACCAACAUUAUAUGCACUCGUGCCUUCAAUGUGGAAUCAAACUGGUUAACCUCAGCACAGUCCUCUCGUUUCUGUGUUUCUGCUGCACUAAUUGCCAGGGGGUGGGGGAGAAGGCGAAUGAAUUAAUUCAUAGUAGAAGGAGGCGAUAGGUGCAGCAAAGGGCAGCCACAGUGUUGAUUCCACAUUAUAAUGUUGUUGCCUCUUCUUGGCAAAAGACACCACAUUGUGGGAAGAUCUCAGCUUCCAGGGUAAAAGUUAAUUUAUAACUUAAAAGUGCUAUUAAGUUUUUAUUACCAAAUAUAUCUUUUAUGGUUUAUAUUGUAGUGGUAUGUAUGAAACAUUUAAAAUUUUACUGUGGAAAUUGUGUAUAUAUAUAUAUAUAGUCGAAAUAGGUGUUCACAGGUCACAUGUGAACGGAGAACUGCAUGACCGUACAUGAAAUGCAAUAAACCAACUGGAAAAAGUGCAUGUGCUUCAUCCUCUCAAGCCAACUGCAGCUGGAAAGUGCUGCUUAUCCUCCACCCCCAGAAAAUGCAUGUAUCAAUAUGAGAAUAAAGAACGCACACUUUCAAUUUUAUUGAGGCUUUCAACACUAUUUAAAAGAAAAUGUAAGAAUUUGACAUUCUGGAGUUAUUAUAACAUUAGAAAAUGAGCAUAACAUUCACUCUGAUUUUAGCCAUUAAGGGAGAUUAGUAAACAGACUGCUACAGUGUUCCAUAGUUGGACUGUGCAUCCAAAACAUUUUUUUAUCUUUAAUAAAUGGUACAGUUUUUAUGUAGUUUUCGAAUGUAAGAAGAAAGGAAUGCUGACCAAAACUUGAUUUCAUCAGCUUCAUGAAAAGGACUAGUGUCAUUAACCUGUUGAACAGAAUUGGUUUAUUAAAAAAAUCAUUUCCAGUAGUGUGAAACCUUUACGAGUCUUUAACAUCUAAAUGUUAUGACUCCUUGUACCUUAAGUUUUCCAGUCUUUCUUAUUUAUAUCAUCUCCAAGUACCUCUGGCUCCUUUCCUCUUGCUCACCGGAACCUUAGUUUUCCUCAACAGAAUGCUUUGUUAAAGUAGCCCACAGUUGCAGGAUCCAUAGCACCGUCGUGCAGACUAGCAGCCCAAAGGUGUGUUUGGUUUGGCUUAUACGGUGUUUUGCUUUUUAAACUACUUGCCAUAAUUUAAAAGUGGCAACACUAGACUUAAAAAAAAAAAAGUCUGAUUGCCCAUAUUAGAUUUUUUUUUUAAUUCUUCACAAAAUCUGCUCUUCCUGAAAGAUCAAAGUGUCUAGAAAGCCCAAACAUGUAUUCUUAACAUAGUAGGCACCAGCUGAAACUGAGUAAUUAAACGGUCCCCUGAAGCCAAGUAUUCCCUGGUUAGUCGCCACCCCACCACUCCUUCCUGUCUCUAGUGUCACACUUGGGCUGUUGAUUUUCUUACUCUUCUCUUGCUUUAAUCCUUCCCCCCGGCUCUCUGGCUCCUGUGGAUAUCUGUGCUUGUUUCCUGGUCCAGGAUGGUGAUCUGACUUUCAAACCAGCUUCUCAAAAGGGGUGACAUAAAAUCAGUUUUGAUGUUUUUCCUCCUGAAAAAUCAGAUGAAUAUUUUAGUCACUGUUACUCAUGCACAUUGUGUUCUUAUGUUUACAGAAGUGCUUAAGUGAAUGGAAGCACUAGACAUUUGGAUUUCCUUCCUAACGUAAUUUUUAAUGAUUACCCCUUUUAUACAGUAAUUUGUGGUCUUUAGAAAGCAGUUAAACUAAUUGACCAUCUAAUAGUUGUACUAUACAUAUGUCUAAAAUAAUAGUCAUGGUAAGUUUGGCAUCAUAUCUUCCCCAAAAAAUGUUUAUUAAAAUUAGAUUAUUCCAGUUUAAUGCUAUUUUGUGAACUGUAUACCCUCUGAAAGCGCUUAUUUUUACAUGCUACACAACAGUUCCAAUUUUAAGGAGUGUCUCCUAAAAUUGGGAUGAAAAUCUACUGUAGUCUGUUUUAAAGUAUGCUAUACUAUGUUCAUUGGUUACUUAACUGGAUAUUAAUAUAAAGGUUAUUACAAGAAAAAUGAUGAAGAGCAAAAGGAGAAGAAAAUAUUUGCAAGUGAAUCCACAAUUCUUGCAGAACUAUUUGAGUUGAUACUAAAGAUUUUAUGUUCACUCCUUUACCUUAGAACUGUCAAGCUUGGGAAUGAGGAAAGUGCCUUGGCUGUGCUUGAAACCUGAAUUUUAGUGCUUCCCUUAUUACAUUCAUUGUUUUCAAUGAUUGAUUUAUAAAAUUAAGACAUACUGGUAGUACAAGUUGAAAGUUGGUUUGAAUACAUUUUAAUUAAAUGAUAAUAUGUUAAUAUGCUUUUGUUCAUUGCUUUCUCACUGAGGUAAAACAGCAUUAAAAAGUUGUCCAGAAUUUAAA